AGACAAGCGGCCAGCCUUGACACGUGACCCAAGCCCCAGCUUCGCGCAGGGAUGGAGCCGGAAGAGGGGACGCCCUUGUGGCGGCUGCAGAAGCUGCCGGCCGAGCUGGGCCCGCAGCUUCUUCACAAAAUAAUUGAUGGCAUUUGUGGUCGAGCUUAUCCUGUGUACCAAGAUUAUCACACUGUUUGGGAAUCAGAAGAAUGGAUGCACGUUUUAGAAGAUAUUGCCAAAUUUUUCAAAGCCAUAGUUGGUAAAAACUUACCUGAUGAAGAGAUAUUUCAGCAGUUGAAUCAGUUGAAUUCACUUCAUCAAGAAACUAUCAUGAAAUGCGUGAAAAGUAGGAAAGAUGAAAUCAAACAGGCUCUGUCAAGAGAAAUAGUUGCUAUUUCCUCUGCACAGCUACAGGAUUUUGAUUGGCAGGUAAAGCUUGCACUUUCCAGUGACAAGAUUGCUGCAUUACGAAUGCCACUUUUAAGCCUGCAUCUAGAUGUAAAAGAAAAUGGUGAAGUAAAACCUUAUUCUAUUGAAAUGAGUAGAGAGGAGCUGCAGAAUCUAAUACAGUCCUUGGAAGCAGCGAAUAAGGUGGUCCUGCAGUUGAAAUAACUGGAAAUGAUGAAUACCAGUCCUAUCAGAUUUUAUUGCUCCAACUUAUAUGGCAGAGUGAAUACUGCGUGUUCAGAAACCUUGUGAUGUCUUGACUGUUGCACCAGGCUGAGAAAGCAGCAAUAUUGAUAUUAUAAAGAUAAAAAUUUAUCAACAUUCCUUAACAGGAAAUUACAUGGUUGAGAGGAAAUGCAUAAAAUGAAAGAUGAAAAAUCUAUAGUAGCAGUUUAUAUUUUCAUGAUUGUUUUGCCUCAUUUAUUAAAUAUUUGAGAAAUCUUUGGAGAUACAUAGUUUUAUUGAAAGCUAAAAAUAGGUUCUAAAGUAAUGUAAAAAUAUAAAGCACAAAUAUACUUGAAUAUUGCUUAAAGAAUUGUGUGAAUAGCAACAUAUAUUAUGGAUAUAUACUUUGUGAUAUUUUUAAAAAAUAAUUUUUUCAAAGAAUGUAUAAGCUGCAUAUAUAACUCAGGAGAUUCCAUGUCUUUCUCAUAUUUCAGAGGAAAGAUUAUAAAAUAUAAAAUUUCUUAGAGAACACCUCUUUGUCAGAGAUAAACAAGAACAAAUACUCUAAACUUAUGUGAACAGUUUUGAGUUUAUGAAUUCUAGAAACUAAAAUCAAGAAUACAGAAAAAUGAAAAUAACAUUUUACUUCUGCGCUUCUAUGUUUGGGAAACAUUGCUCUGAUAAAAAAUAGCUGUCAUUAUGCAGUGUGUAUAUUCAAAUAUGAGAUAAGACUAUGUACACAUCCACUUUUGUUAAUAAACUCAAUAUUGAAUACUUUGGGAUGUUAAAUUCAUUGGAAAAACAAACCAUUUGUAACCUCAGUUAACUUUAACAACAAGCAUUCUGAGCAAAUGAAAA